UGUGUUUAAAAUCCACAUACUGAUAGCAAAUCUUUGGUUGAAACAGUAUUAAAUUACUGGGGCUUCCAGUGGCUGAGUCCAACUUAAUUUGAAGUUUCAGAUUAAGUAUCAGGAGGAAUAACUUGAUAUUUAGAGCCAACAGGUCUUUCUUUUUUUUUUAAACCUCCCAAAAAACCUAUAAAAUCAAGAAUUGGCGGGGAGGACCGGAGAAUGAUAAAGGAAUAGUUGACUGAUUUAUAGAAACUUUUAGUGGCGGUAAAAAUUACAAAAGUAUUGGAAAUAAGGCAAAAGGACAGCAUGUUUUUUUCAGAGUCAAAAUGGAGCCUAACAGGCCCACCUGAAGAUGAUUUAGAUGUCUAGGGGACUAUAUUUUGUUUGGCAUGAUGAUAUUGAUUAGGGCCUAGGCUUUGUAGUUAACAUCUUUUUCAUUAAUGGAGAUGCAAAUUAUUUCUGAGUGGGAGAGAAAAAAAUACAGUACUCCUAAAGGUUGUAGUUUUAGUGCCUUGUAGGAUAUUAGCCAUUUUUCUUUUCUUUUUUUUGAGACAGAGUCUUGCUCUGUCGCCCAGGCUGGAGUGCAGUGGCACGAUCUCGGCUCACUGCAACCUCUGCCUCUCGGGUUAAAGCAAUUCUCCUGCCUCAGCCUCCCGAGUUGCUGGGACUACAGGUGCCCGCCACCACGCUCAGCUAAUUUUUGUAAGUUUAGUAGAGACGGGGUUUCACCAUAUUGGCCAGGCUGGUCCGGAACUCCUGAUUUUGUGAUCCGCCUGCCUCGGCCUCCCAAAGUACUGGGAUCACAGGCGUCAGCCACCGCGCCCGGCCAAUAUUAACCAUUUUUCUGUCUAACCUAUCAAACUUACCAUCCUUUCUUCAGUGUUUAUGCUCAGUUCCUGAAAUGCUUUUGAGCACACUAAGCCAUUCAGCUUGUUCCAUUGUGAGUUUAAUAAAUCUUUGUCACAGGUUCAUUUUGAGUCAUAUUUAUAACUUUUGUUAUUGGACAAUGGUCUCUAUUCUUUAGUGGCAAAAACAAGUUUAUGCUUCUCAGGAUGGAAGGACAUAGGCCCUGUGUGGUACUCAAAUACAUCUUAGGACUCCAAGUAGAAUCCUUUCUCAUUGCUUCAGAAAGGUUAAACAGUGACCAGAGGAAAUGUUACAGAACUUUGACCAAAAAAUAAAUCCUGAGUAUUGAGAAAUUAAAAUUAAAGUCUUGCAAAUUGCAGAGUUUAAAAAUUGUUAUUGAUAUUUUAAAUUGAAGAAAUUAGUGGAAAUAGUAGUUCUAAAUUGCAUACAUUUGAAUGUGGAGUGUUAAAAGAUUAUUUCCCUUGUCUCCUGUUUUAUUUAGGAUAAGGUUAACUGAGAUUUUGGUACAUGGUGGGCCAUUCAAGUUAUGUAUAAUGUUUUGUGACAAACUACAUGUCGACAGUAGUUCCUGAUGCCUAAUACAUUUCUGAGAAAGUAGAGACGGGGUUUCACCGUGUUAGCCAAGAUGGUCUCGAUCUCCUGACCUCGUGAUCCGCCCGCCUCGGCCUCCCAAAGUGCUGGGAUUACAGGCGUGAGCCACUGCGCCCGGCCUGUUGUACAGUUAUUAAAGUUAUCAUUUAACAUGGAAGAAGAUGAGUUCAUUGGAGAAAAAACAUUCCAACGUUAUUGUGCAGAAUUCAUUAAACAUUCACAACAGAUAGGUGAUAGUUGGGAAUGGAGACCAUCAAAGGACUGUUCUGAUGGCUACAUGUGCAAAAUACACUUUCAAAUUAAGAAUGGGUCUGUGAUGUCACAUCUAGGAGCAUCUACCCAUGGACAGACAUGUCUUCCCAUGGAGGAGGCUUUCGAGCUACCCUUGGAUGAUUGUGAAGUGAUUGAAACUGCAGCAGCGUCCGAAGUGAUUAAAUAUGAGUAUCAUGUCUUAUAUUCCUGUAGCUACCAAGUGCCUGUACUUUACUUUAGGGCAAGCUUUUUAGAUGGGAGACCUUUAACUCUGAAGGACAUAUGGGAAGGAGUUCAUGAGUGCUAUAAGAUGCGACUGCUACAGGGACCAUGGGACACUAUUACGCAACAGGAACAUCCAAUACUUGGGCAACCCUUUUUUGUACUUCAUCCCUGCAAGACGAAUGAAUUCAUGACUCCUGUAUUAAAGAAUUCUCAGAAAAUCAAUAAGAAUGUCAACUAUAUCACAUCAUGGCUGAGCAUUGUAGGGCCAGUUGUUGGGCUGAAUCUACCUCUGAGUUAUGCCAAAGCAACGUCUCAGGAUGAACGAAAUGUCCCUUAACAAGAUUCUUCUAUUGAGUUUAGGAAUUGCGGCACGAAGAAUGCCAAGAGUUUACCUGGCCAGCCCUGGCUUUAAUAGGACUGAUACCAUGGAAUAUUUCAUCUCACCAAGAUGUGACAUGGAUUAUUUUUCCCUUGGACACAAAUGUCUACAGCAACUGGUGUUUGAUAGGCUGAAUGUUUAGAAGAAACACUUCAAAGGGAUACAUCAUGGCCAGGCAUGGUGGCUCACACCUGUAAUCCAAGCACUUUGGGAGGCCAAGGUGGGAGCAUCACUUGAUCCUGGGAGUUCGAGACCAGCCUGGGCAACAUGGUGAAACCCUGUCGGUACAAAAAAAUACAAAAAUUUGCCUGUUUAUGGUGGUGUGUUCCUGUAGUCCCAGCUCCCCAGGAGGCUGAGGUGGGAGGUUGGCUUUAACCCAGGAGGCAGAGGUUGCAGUGAGCUGAGACUGUGCCACUGCAGUCCAGCCUGGGUGACAGAGCCAGACACUGUCUCGGGGAAAAAAAAAAAAAAAAAAAGACACAUCACUAUAAAUAGCAAAAAAACAAAUCUAACUUAUUAAUACUAGGAAUACCAACAUUAUUAGGGCACUUGCAGGUUAUUCUUUUCUAGGCCAAGUACUUCACUUCCAUUUGUCUGACAUGGAGAUUGAGGGAGAAAUGUAUUUGUGUGUUCAUUUUAAUGUAAGAUAUAUAAAAAUUAAAUUACUGGAUUUACCUGUCCCUGAAACUGGUGUUAUAAACAUGACCUAUCUUAAGUGAUUUUCCCACAAUCAAACUCAGGAACAAUAGAUUAUUUCUGUUUUACUCCAAAAGAGAGAGAGAGAGUGAGUGUGAGUGUGUGUGUGUGUGUGUGUGUAUGUGUGGGUGUUUGUGUAGAUAGUUGUAAAACAAAGAAAAAACACAAUAUUUUACUGUGAGAUAAUAUGUUUUACCAGCAAAGUGUGGCAUAGUAAUUAGAAGUUUUCUAAAAAGCUAUAGGAGAUAUUUAAACAUUAAAAUUUCUUUUUGACCUAUAGUAAUAAAACAAUGGUCAUUUUACCCCUCUGCUUCUCAACCCCACAGCUGCUCUGCUGUACUCUUUGAGGGCUCUUGAGCGAGUCUUCAUGUCCCUGAGACUUAUUUUCCUCAUCUUUAAUUUGAAACUAACAAGCUACCUCAUAGGGUUGCUGUGAGAACCACAUGAGAUCAUUAAUGCAUGAUAAGAUAUUGUAAAGUAUUAUACGAAUAUUCAUUAAAUGCUCACCUUUCUUGUAUAUAAUUGGUAUUCACUAAGGCUGUAAAUAAGUUUCAUAGCCAGUUAAGUAUUAAGAUAAACCUAACCUGGAACAAUUUUUUUUUUGGUUGCUUGUUUUGUUUUUUGCUUUCAUUUGCUAGGAGCUGAAACGAAGAUUAAAAUGUCAUUGGCUUUUUAGAGAGUCUAGAUUAGUGUGUCUUUGAAUGAGGGAUAUACUUAAAAUCACCUGAGGAUCGUUUACAGCUACAGAUGCUGGGGCCACCUGACACAGUCUCUCUGGGGGUGAUUCUGCUCUGGAGAACCUCUGGUCUGGAUAUACCUUUAUUGUGACAUUGAUUUGUAUUGUUUUGCUCUACUGACAGGCCUUUUCCAAUCCAUACAAGCUGAACUUGCUUCCUAAUGUUUGUCUAGGCCUUACAUGGAUAGUAAGGAAGCUUAGGAGACAUGUACACAAGGCAGCCCACUUGUAGGAAACUGCUUCAGGUGAGGACAUCAUUCACCAGUGGAUCACCGAGCACCGUGACAGCACCCUCAGUCCACGUCUGCAGAUUAAGAGCUGAACUCUCACAGAGAAAGUGGAAGUAGAGAAAGGGUUAAUUCAAACUGCUAGAAAAGCUAAAAGUAAAUUUUAAAAUGCUGAGCUGCCCAUAUUCAUGCUAGGAUGAGAGCCGGCUUAAAUGCUUGCUGGGCAUUUUGGUAUUUACCACUUAGCAUGUUUUCAACUUCUGUGAGGGAUUUUCCCCCCAAUCUCCCUAAUGUAAACACAGAUUUCUCAGCAAGUCAUUUCUCAAGCCAUGUCAUUUCUAGUGUAAAAUAAAUUAUAAUAAUGUGUCA